GCCCAUUUUGCUGGCCUGAGGCUGAAGAGAGGGUUGAUAGGAUGAAUGGCAGGAUAAAAUCUUCCUUCCUUGAAACCACAUAGCUUCUGACAAGCAAAGAUGUCACUUGAUAUUCUUGGCUUGAUGAAAAAAGAACAAGAUUCUAAUGUGACAGAAUUUGUUCUUCUGGGCCUAUCAUCUUCUUGGGAGCUGCAGCUAUUUCUCUUCUUACUAUUUUUGUUUUUUUACAUUGCUAUUGUCCUGGGAAACCUCUUGAUAGUGGUAACAGUGCAAGCCCAUGCUCACCUGCUCCAAUCUCCUAUGUAUUAUUUUUUAGGUCAUCUCUCUUUCAUUGACCUAUGCCUGAGCUGUGUUACUGUGCCAAAGAUGUUAGGGGAUUUCCUACAGCAGGGCAAGAGCAUCUCUUUUUCAGGAUGCCUGGCCCAGAUCUACUUCCUCCACUUUCUAGGAGCCAGUGAGAUGUUUUUGCUGACAGUCAUGGCCUAUGACAGGUAUGUUGCCAUCUGUAACCCUUUGCGCUACCUUACAGUCAUGAACCCCCAGCUAUGCCUUUGGUUGGUUCUUGCCUGCUGGUGUGGGGGUUUUAUCCACUCUAUCAUGCAGGUCAUACUAGUCAUCCAGCUGCCUUUCUGUGGGCCCAAUGAACUGGACAACUUCUACUGUGAUGUCCCACAAGUCAUCAAGCUGGCCUGCAUGGACACCUAUGUGGUAGAGGUGCUGGUGAUAGCCAACAGUGGUCUGCUGUCUCUUGUCUGCUUCUUGGUCUUACUAUUCUCUUAUGCUAUCAUCCUGAUCACCCUGAGAACACACUUCUGCCAGGGCCAGAACAAGGUCUUCUCUACCUGUGCUUCUCACCUGACAGUGGUCAGCCUGAUCUUCGUGCCAUGCGUAUUCAUCUAUUUGAGGCCUUUCUGCAGCUUCUCUGUGGAUAAGAUAUUCUCCUUGUUUUACACAGUGAUUACACCUAUGUUGAACCCCCUCAUCUACACACUCAGAAAUACUGAUAUGAAGACAGCUAUGAAGAAGCUGAGGAUAAAACCAUGUGGCAUUCCAUUGCCUUGUUAAGGAAUGAGCAGAAGAGGUGAUUUGAAAAACACACUCUUUCUUGGAAGACUCUUAACUCAUCUUGUACAUGGGUAAAAACCACUUUGAUGACGUUGGUAUAAAAGAGGAGAUAGCAUAAAGAUUAUAAUGGAUCACUCUUGAUUACAAUUUAAAAGCAUAGGUGGCACUCUAGAAAGCCACCUAUGCCUUUUGACCAUAAUCAAGAGAACUCAGGAACUCAGUAGAAUUUACUGGCCACAAACGAUAACAAGCAUUAAUUGAAAGAUCAACUUUUCUAUCUUUAUGUCUCUAAGUACUGUUCAUUUAUUCAAUUUUUUCCACUUUUUAAUCUAUUCAAAUGAAAGAAGAUAUAUCUCUUUUUGUGUUCAGUUCCUCCAGCAUUUAAUGAUUCCUAGUGUUAGGAAGUUCCUUCUGAUGUCUCAUCAGAUCCUUUUCUGAAGUAGUGUGAAUUUCUUUGUUCUGUUAUAACAAAGCCUGAGAACAGUAACAACCACCUAUGUGUAGUAUUUACCUCAGAACUGUGUUCCACAGUGUCCCAAGUUUUAGAAAUGUAGUCAGGCAUCAGUCUAAUGAACAUAUGCUCUUAACAAAGUUUAUGCGUGAGAGAAAGGAAGUCCAGGAGUGCAGGGGUGAUGGAAGCUGUUAGUAUUCUGUUGUAGAGGCUUCUCAAGAAGAGGUACCUAGUUUCACACUGAGUUUUUCUUUGAUUGGAAUUACAGUGGGGGUGAAUAGAUAAGCUGGCUCUUCAACUGACCAUAAUGUUUAAGAGUUUUAACCUCUAAAGGAACAGAGGAAGAAAUGAACUGUGAUUGAAAGCACUCAUUUUUGAGAUGCUCACAGUUAUUACCUCUGAGUCUCAAACAUGCUUUGAGGAAUAAAUUUACUUAACUUCAUUUUUGAGAAUGAACUCAGAGUUAAGUGACUUGCCCAUGACCACUUAGAAGAAAUGCAAUCAAUCAAGAAAGCUCUUUGUAAUCCCAGCACUUUGGGAGGCCAGGGCAGGCAGAUCAUCUGAAGUCAGGAGUUUGAGACCAGCUUGAGCAAUAUGGAGAAACCCCGUCUCUACUAAAAAUACAAAAUUAGCCGGACGUGGUGUUGCA